UAUUGAACCUAAUUUGUACCAUACUCUUUGCUGAGUACCAAGGAGGUUAAACUAAAUAAGUAAAGAAAUGGUCUCUGCUCUCAAGGAGCCUGUAGAGGAGUUGUAGUCUUUCCUCCUCCCAGCCCCCUGCCCUCCAAAAAAAAAAAAAAAAAAAAAGGAAAAGAAAAAACAUCCUGAAACACUCAGAGGAUCACAAGGUGCUGAAAAAAUGCCCAGGUAAAAUUAUUACUGGAGACAUUUGACCUGGAAAAAAGAAAUCAGCUGAAGAGGCUAAGGUGGCAGUAUUCGAAGGCUGACAUUCGACAAAAGAAUGAGACUUAUUUUGUAUAGCCUUAGAAAGCAGAAUCUACCUCUCUGACCUUAUCACUAAGAGUGACAGAAGGAAGUCAAGGCACCAUUAUGACUCGGAUGAGAAAUCAGAAACAAGAGAAAAUGGUGUUACAGAUGACCUGGAUGCUCCCAAGGCCAAAAAAUCUAAAAUGAAAGAGAAGCUAAAUGGAGACACUGAAGAAGGAUUUAAUAGACUUUCAGAUGAAUUCUCCAAAUCUCAUAAGUCAAGAAGAAAAGAUCUACCAAAUGGAGAUAUAGAUGAAUAUGAAAAAAAAUCAAAGCGAGUAUCAUCUUUAGAUACUUCUACUCAUAAAUCAAGUGAUAAUAAACUAGAGGAGACCUUAACACGUGAACAGAAAGAAGGAGCCUUCUCCAAUUUUCCUAUUUCUGAAGAGACUAUAAAGCUUCUGAAAGGUCGAGGGGUAACAUAUCUCUUUCCUAUUCAAGUUAAGACCUUUGGUCCUGUAUAUGAAGGAAAAGAUUUAAUAGCUCAAGCACGGACAGGAACAGGAAAGACAUUCUCUUUUGCCAUCCCCUUAAUUGAAAGACUCCAAAGAAAUCAAGAAACAAUUAAAAAAAGCCGCUCACCAAAGGUACUUGUUUUGGCUCCAACAAGGGAACUGGCAAACCAAGUAGCCAAAGACUUCAAAGAUAUAACUAGGAAACUCAGCGUGGCGUGUUUUUAUGGUGGAACAUCAUAUCAAAGCCAAAUUAAUCAUAUUCGAAAUGGUAUUGACAUCUUGGUUGGAACACCUGGUCGUAUCAAAGACCAUCUGCAGAGUGGCCGAUUGGAUCUUUCUAAACUGCGACAUGUUGUGCUUGAUGAAGUGGAUCAGAUGUUAGAUUUAGGUUUCGCUGAACAAGUUGAAGAUAUUAUUCAUGAAUCCUACAAAACUGAUUCUGAAGACAAUCCUCAGACUUUACUUUUUUCUGCAACUUGCCCACAGUGGGUAUACAAAGUUGCAAAAAAAUACAUGAAAUCCAGAUAUGAACAGGUUGACCUUGUUGGAAAAAUGACUCAAAAGGCUGCAACUACUGUGGAACAUUUGGCCAUCCAGUGUCAUUGGUCUCAGAGGCCAGCAGUUAUUGGAGAUGUCCUUCAAGUCUACAGUGGGUCUGAAGGGAGGGCUAUUAUUUUCUGUGAGACCAAGAAGAAUGUAACUGAAAUGGCCAUGAAUCCACACAUAAAACAGAAUGCCCAGUGUUUACAUGGGGACAUUGCACAGUCACAAAGAGAAAUUACACUAAAAGGCUUCAGAGAAGGUAGUUUUAAAGUUUUGGUGGCAACCAAUGUGGCUGCCCGUGGUUUGGACAUUCCUGAAGUUGACCUGGUGAUUCAAAGUUCUCCUCCUCAGGAUGUUGAGUCCUAUAUCCAUCGCUCUGGACGCACAGGUAGAGCUGGACGGACAGGGAUUUGUAUAUGUUUUUAUCAACCAAGAGAAAGAGGUCAACUAAGAUAUGUGGAACAAAAAGCAGGAAUUACUUUUAAACGUGUAGGUGUUCCUUCUACAAUGGAUUUAGUUAAAUCUAAAAGCAUGGAUGCCAUCAGGUCUCUGGCUUCCGUUUCUUACGCUGCUGUUGAUUUUUUCCGACCAUCAGCUCAGAGACUGAUAGAAGAGAAAGGUGCAGUGGAUGCAUUGGCUGCAGCUUUAGCCCACAUUUCUGGUGCAUCAAGCUUUGAACCACGAUCUUUGAUCACCUCUGAUAAGGGGUUUGUGACCAUGACUCUGGAAAGCCUAGAGGAAAUACAGGAUGUCAGCUGUGCUUGGAAAGAACUUAACAGAAAGCUGAGUAGUAAUGCAGUGUCUCAGAUUACCAGAAUGUGCCUCCUGAAAGGAAAUAUGGGUGUUUGCUUUGAUGUUCCUACAACUGAGUCAGAAAGGUUACAGGCAGAGUGGCAUGAUUCCGACUGGAUACUCUCAGUGCCAGCCAAAUUACCUGAAAUUGAAGAAUAUUAUGAUGGAAACACAUCUUCUAAUUCCAGACAGAGGAGUGGCUGGUCAAGUGGUCGAUCAGGCCGGUCAGGCCGGUCAGGUGGUCGAUCUGGCGGCCGGUCAGGUAGACAGAGUCGACAAGGAAGUCGCUCAGGAAGUCGACAAGAUGGUAGAAGACGAAGUGGGAAUAGAAAUCGAUCAAGAAGUGGGGGCCACAAACGGAGUUUUGACUGAGUAUUUGAUAGUUAAUCUACCAGUGUGAGCUUGCCUAUUUCUGCCUAAUCAUGUACAUUAUCCACCAAAAAUUAGGUCAUCAUAGUUGAGGUAUGUGUCUGCUAUUUGCAAAGAAGUUGGUCGUAUUUUUUUAAAAAGUAUUUCACAAGAAUGGAACAAAUCUACUUAUCCAGUUAUACCUUUGAAUAAAAAAACCUCCUUUUAUUGUCUCUUUUCA